GACUUCCGGUCGGCGUGAGCGUGAGGUGUGGGUGUUCGUUUCUCAGGUAAAACAUGGCUAAAAGCUUACGGAGUAAGUGGAAAAGAAAGAUGCGUGCUGAAAAGAGAAAAAAGAAUGCCCCAAAGGAGGCCAGCAGGCUUAAAAGUAUUCUCAAACUAGACGGUGAUGUUUUAAUGAAAGAUGUUCAAGAGAUAGCAACUGUGGUGGUACCCAAACCCAAACAUUGCCAAGAGAAAAUGCAAUGUGAGGUAAAAGAUGAAAAAGAUGACAUGAAAAUGGAGACUGAUAUUAAGAGAAACAAAAAGACUCUUCUAGACCAGCAUGGACAGUACCCAAUAUGGAUGAACCAAAGGCAAAGAAAAAGGCUGAAGGCAAAGCGAGAGAAAAGAAAGGGGAAAAGCAAAGCAAAAGCAGUGAAAGUGGCAAAGGGUUUGGCCUGGUAGACUCUUAAAACCUUGGAAAAUGCCACAUGGGAUAGAUGACGGAUUAGAAUGUAUACACAUGUAUACUUUGAUUUCAACUGCCACCAAAUGAAAACCAUUUGUUUUCCUAUUUUAACUUGGCCUUUUUUCUUCAAUUCAAACCCAGCAUAACUCCUCAAGUUUGUUUUGGGAACUUGAAUAAAAUAUUUUCUUUGAUACAUCCAAGCUCUACUGAUACUUUAACUGGAUGCUACCCAAUAUCCAGUUAUAAUCAGGCCUCAACGUUCUGUCAGGUAUUAAUAUGGUUAGAAUUGUUCUUACAACUGGUAAUUAUAGUCAAUAGAGAUAAAACAGAUGAUGUACUGACAAAUUUUUGUGAACUUAGAUUUUAAAGAAAGUUGUUGUAUAAUCAUAUCAUUUAAAAAUACUACAUUAGGGCUGGGCAUGGUGGCUCACACCUGUAAUCCCAGCACUUUGGGAGGCCGAGGCAGGUGGAUCACGAGGUCAGUUCGAGACUAGCCUGGCUAAUACAGUGAAACCCCAUCUCUACUAAAAAUACAAAAUUAGCCGGGCAUGGGGGCGCGCACCUGUAGUUCCAGCUACUCGGGAGGCUGAGGCAGGAUAAUUGCUUGAACCCAGGAGAUGGAGGUUGCAGUGAGCCAAGAUUGCCCCACUGCACUCCACCCUGGGCAAUGGAGUAGGACUCUGUCUCAAAAAAAAAAAAAAUAAUGGAUCUUAUAAAGUACUUGUGUGGAGCUUUGAUUCCACAGAAUAAAAGAUAUUUUGUGUGUAGAUCUUCAAGUCUGAUUUUUUUUUCUUUCAUGUAUGCUUAAGGUUUUUUAGUCCUAGAGAAGACCAGAUUUCAAUUAAAUGUUUUCUUAUCUUAAUUUUAGGUAGAAUAUUAACAUAUACAAAUCAGUAUGCUUUUUAGGAAAUUAGAACAUUUCAGGUUUUUCAUGGAAACUGAUUUAAUGUUCUUUAGUGUUAAUAUUGUGUGGCCUAAUAUAGUAUCAUGCAGCAUUCCCCGGAGUGUGUUCUUCAGUAUCAGUUUCCUCUGGAUGCUUGGUUAAAAAAAAUAAAUUGUGUUCACAUCGAUUUGGGAAAUGCUACAUACUUGAAGAUUUACAAAAGAUUUUAGUUUAGGAUUAGAAUAGUCCUACAGGGUUCCAGCAGCAAAGAAACCUGUUUAGCGUCUACUCUUUGAAACUAGUUUUCUGAGAAAUGAUUUUUAGUUAAAUCUGUCUUACUACAGUUUGCUAAAUUCAUUUUUAUUUUACUUUUAGUUAAGCAAUCUAAACUUAGCAUUCCCUCUGAAUUUCACUAUAAUCAGAUUAACCAUCUCAUAUGUUAACUGGAACAACCAAAUACUUACUGAGUGCCUAGUAUGUGGGCCAGGGACUUUCCAGAUGCUUGGGACAGAUUGAAUAAGAUAAGAUUUCUGCUCUCAUAGGGCUGAGAGCUGUGUAUCUGUUUAGAAGAAGAUGUUAACUUCCCAGGAGAACUCAAGUAAAAUGUGAAAUAGAAUAAGGCCACUUGGUCAUGAGGUCACAAACUUUGUGCCAGGCACACUGCUAAAUUGGGGCACAAUACAUGGACAUGUAUUGUAAUAAAGAGGACAUGACCCAAAUGUUUCAGAAAAUUUAAGCUUAUAAAAUUUGAUGCCAGUAAACUCUUGGAAUUGUUUAAAUAUAGUAGACUUUUCUUAUUUUUCUCAAUAGUUUAUUGAAAAGUUGGUAGAUAACUUUAAAUGCUUAAAAUUUCUUAACAGCUAAGAAAGAUAUGAAUUGAAAGAUGUCAUUCAUGAUCUUUGUUGCCUUUGGUGUAGGUAUGAAUAACACUAGCAUUUGUGAGGGAAAAGUGAAUAUGUACAUUUUUAUUCAUAAAAUAAAAAAAAUUGCAAACAACCAGUUAAGCCACUGACAAUAUCAGCCUAAAUACAGUAGCUGAAUUAUUUAUGUUUUUUUUUUUUUUUUUUUUGAGAUGGGGUCUCACUCUGUCACCCAGGCUGGAGUGAUUGGCACAAGUGUGGCUCCGCUGCAACCUCCACCUCCCAGGCUGAAGCGAUUCUCCCACCUCAGCCUCCCCAGUAGCUGGGACUACAGGUGGGUGCCACCACGCCCAGCUAAUUUUUGUAUUUUUGUAGAGACAGGGUUUCGCCAUGUUGCCCAGGCUGGUCUCAAACUCCUGGACUCAAGUAAUCCACCUGCCCCAGCCUCCCAAAGUGGUGGGAUUACAUGCGUGAGCCACCACACCCGGCCUAAUGUAGACAUUUUUUAUGAUUUUUGGAAAAGGGGGCCAGGCACCAAAUUCUAACAAUUUGGGAGGCUGAGGCAGAUGGAUCACCUGAGGUCAGGAGUUUGAGACCAGCCUGACCAACAUGGUGAAACCCUGUCUCUACUAAAAAUACAAAGUUAGCUGGGCAUGGUGGCAGGUGCCUGUAAUCCCAGCUACUUGGGAGGCUGAGGAAGGAGAAUCGCUUGAACCUGGGAGGCAGAGGUUGCAGUGAGUCAAGACCACACCAUUGCACUCCAGCCUGAGCAAGAAGAGCGAAACUCCAUCUCAAAAAAAAAAAAAAAAAAAGUCUACAUUCGUGAUAUUACACAGUUGGCACUUAUUUACAUUUUGGCAGCAUUGUCAGGUAGAGACCAAUGCCAGGGUUAUGUUCAUGUUUUCUGUGGCUGAUAACCUCUAAUUUGAUUCUGUUGAUAGUAGCUUUGAGCUUUCAUCCAGAGCCUCUCUGAUGUUAGGAUUUUCACUUCAUUGUGUCCAGUCAUGAAGUUUGUCCAUUCAGGAUUUAACUUGAAAGUUAACAAAAUCAAAAAUCAAAGCACCAUUACCAGAAAACAUAUUUGGGAAUCAUGUUCUCAAGUGUCACAUGGCCUCUGGAAAGGCGACUGCUGAAGAGAAGUUUACUGACACAGUGUUGUCAGUACCCUCUAAGGCACUGAGUUCCUGAACACUACCAGCAAGAUUCUCCCCACCUCCAAAUAUUGGCAGGAAAUUUAGACUAGCAUUUCAAAAUUAGUGCAGGGGUAUGGUCACAUCUUUGGCACUUUAUUUUUAAAGAUUACAAAUCGAGAAGUAUAGCAUAGUCCUUUUAUCUUUUAAAUAAUUAGCUUAUUUUUUUGAAAUUUGUCAUCUUUUUGACUGACAUUUUCCAGAGAAUUGCUGUAAAGCCACAAGAUGGAGCUCAAGCUAAGCACCAAAUCAUUUUGGAAUUAGAUUGAGUGAGCUAAAUCACAUUAGGAAUUGAAUGUAACACUUUUUGUGUUUUAAGAAAUUAAGUCUGAAAUCAAAAUAUAAUUUAAAGAUGAUCAAAACUGCUUCAAGUAUUAACUCAUUUAAUCUGCCCAGCAAUCUCAUGAGUUUGGUACUAAUGUUAUCUGAGUUUGGUACUAAUGUAAUCUCUGUUUACACAUGGGGAAACUGAGGCACACAGGCCAUACAACUAAAACUGAAAUCUGGGAUUCAAAUUUAGGCAGUGUGGCUCUAGAGCCUAUACUCUUACAAUGCCAUUCUGCCUCUCAAGGAUGUGCAAACUCUUGCUAAGAGAGAAAGGUGAUUUUAGGAUAGAAUACCUAUUUUUGGGUCAACCUGUGAUAGAUUGGGUUCAUGUGGGCUCAGGAUCAGAUAAAGAGCAGGUUUAAGUAGAAUAAUGAUGUACAGAACCCUCCUCAAAUCUCUAGGCCUAAGGCAGACUGGAUUUCCUCAGGUGACACUUCAUUAGGAAUGGGCUGACCAAUCCAAAAGGGGAAGGUGUAGGCCAUGAUCAGUAGUUGCCCAAGGUACUAAUCAGAGAAGAAAUGCAAACUGCAGUUGAAGCUCUAAGGUAGAAUCAAGUAGUGGUUUUGACCACAUCCUAUUUUCUACUGUCACAUUAGUGUAGAUAUCUCUUCCCACUAUGUAAUUCACAUGCUACAUCAAAUAAGGAUGCAGCAGUAUAUAUUUGCUUAUUAGGAAAUUCAGAUAUUUUCAAAAUUUGGAUCCGUGUUUCUGGAAUAUGGCUUAAGAGUUGGAGAAGAAAAAUAGCUAUAAAUGACUUGAAUCAAAUAUCUGAAAUGGACUGGUGGUGAUGGUGAGGGGCAGCAAUGUGUAAUUUAGGGAAGUGCUGACCACAACAUAAAAUUGGGAGGAAUCUAAGGCAUUGCCAAAUUUAUAAAUACUACAAUAGAAAUGCAGAUGCUAAGCUGUUGGCUAAUCUUACUAGUUAAGUGACUAACUUCUGAUGCCAUCUGGCAGAGUGAUUCAAAUUUGUGCUAAACACAAAAUAUAUGUCUUUUUCCCUCUAUUUGCCUGCAUGUAUUAAUAAAAACACUGUUGCAGUAGACACAUACCAAUUUUACAAGGAAAUGUUUAGGGGUGAGGUGGGACUGUUAAAUACUUACAUCAGGUCAAAGGUCACUCUGCUGUUUCCAGAGGACUGUCAGGUAGCCAGGAGGCCCAGGGCCACUUUUGGGCCUGCUUACAAAACCCUAAAUUUUCCGCAGUUGAAUGCCAAGAGUCUUUUGCAGUUAUUUUAGAGCAGGGGAGAAAAUACAAUGUGUUGCCAAAUAAGCUUAAUUUGGUAGGCAAGCAGUAAAAAUAACCCAACAGCCAACAUUUAGAGAAUGCGUACUCUCUUAAAUGCUUUAUGUAUAUUAUUUAAUCUUUAAAACACUGUGGGAUCAAUACUUUAAUUAUCCCUAUUUUCAGAUGAGAAAACAGUUUGAAAGGUUAACUAAAUUUACCCAAAGUCAUGCAACUGCUAAGUAGUGAGCAAGCCGCCUGUCCCAGAGUAUAGAAUGAAUACCUAUGAUGGAAAGCUACAGAGAGACAGACUUUUAUUUGAUUUAAGGAAGCGCCUUCUAACCAAGAUUUUGGGAGCUGAAAUGGGCACCUUGGGAUCCUUGAGGUGUCAGUCUAAGGUGGACAGGCAUUUGGUUGGAAUGUAGCAAAAUGGAUUCAAACACUGUAGAGUUAUCCUUCAGAAUCUAUCGGGGAUUGGUGCCAGGAUCUUCACAGAUACCAAAAUCCACAGAUGCUCGAAUCGCUUACAUAAACUGGUGAAAUAUUUGCAUAUAACCCAUGCCCAUCCUCCCAUAUAUAGUCAUAUGUCACUAAAUGACUGGGAUGUGUUCUGAGAAGUGUGUCACUAGGUAAUAUCGUUAAUCAUUGUGUGAAUAUCAUAGACUGUACUUACACAAAUCUAGAGGGUAUCGUCUACUACACUUAGGCUAUGUGAUAUAGCCUAUUGCUUCUAGGCUACAAAUUGGUCAAGCAAGUUACUGUACUGAGUACUGUAGGCAAUUGUAUCACAAUGGGAAGUAUUUGUGUAUCUAAACAUAGAAAAGGUACAGUAAAAAUACAGUAUAAAAGAUAAAAAAAUGGUACACCUGUACCACUUAUGAAUAGUGCUUGGAGGACUCGUGCUUGGGGUGAGUCAAUGAGUAAGCCAUGAGUGAAUGUGAAGGCCUCAGACAUGACUGUAUACUGCUGUAUAUUUUUUUUUUUUUUUUUUGAGACGGAGUUUCACUCUUGUUGCCCAGGCUGGAGUACAAUGGCGCAAUCUCAGCUCACCUCAACCUCCACCUCCUGGGUUCAAGCAAUUCUUCUGCCUCAACCUCCCGACUAGCUAGGAUUACAGGCAUGCACCACCACGGCCGGCUAAUUUUGUAUUUUUGGUAGAGAUGAGGUUUCUCCAUGUUGGUCAGGCUGGCCUUGAACUCCUGACCUCAGGUGAUCCACCUGCCUCAGCCUCCCAAAGUGCUGCGAUUACAGGCGUGAGCCACUGUACUCGGCCUGCUGUAGGCUUUAUAUACACUGUGCACUUAGGCUACAUAAACUUAUAAAAAACUUUCUUCAAUAAUAAAUUAACUUUAGCUUCCUGUAACUUUUUUACCUUAUAAACGUUUUAAUUUUUUAAACUGUAUAACCCUUUUAUCAUAACACUUACCUUAAAACACAAAUACAUUGUACAACUGUACACAAAUAUUUUAUAUUUUUAUAAGCUUUUUUCUAUUUCCACAAUUUUUAAUUUUUUAAUUUCUUUUUUUACUUCUUAAGUUUUUUUGUUAAAAACUAAGACACAAACACAUUAGCCUCCAUCUACACUGUCUUCCACCUCCACAGCUUGUCCCACUGCAAGGCCUUCAGGGGCAAUAACAGGCAUGGAGUUGCCAUCUCCUAUGAGAGCAACACCUUCUUGUGCAAUACCUUCUGGAGGACCUGCCUGAGGCUGUUCACAGUCAACUUUUUCUUUAAGUAGAAGGAGUACACUCUAAAAUAAAAAGUAUAGUAAAGCCAUAAACCGUAGUCAUUAUUAUCAAGUAUUAUGAACUGUACAUAAUUGUAUGUGCUAUACCUUUAUAUGACUGACAGCACAGUAGGUUUGUUUACACCAGCAUCACCACAAACACGUGAGUAAUGCAUUGCACUGUGAUGUUAAGAUGGCUACAGUGUCACUGGGCCAUAGGAAUGUUUCAGCUCUACUGUAAUCUUAUGGGACCACUGCCUAUAUUGACUGAAAUGUCAUCAUGCAAUGCAUGACUGUACUUUAAAUCAUCUCUAGAUUACUUAUAAUACAAUGAAAAUGCUAUGUAAAUAGUUGUUAUACUGUAUUUAGGGAAUAAUGAUAAGAAAAAAAGUCGGUACAUGUUCAGUACAGAUGCAACUGUAGUUUUCUUUUGAAUAUUUUUUAUCUCAGGACGAAGCCCCAAAUGCAGAAUUCAUAGAUACAGAGGGCCAACUGUUCUUGGAAUUUGGGUUGAAAGCUGUUAAAGUUCUUUUCAGCCAAAAAAAAAUGCCUCGUAAUAAAUUGUCAUGUUUGAAAUGUAUCAUGCUUGUUUUGCUCUACAUAGUUUUUUGGUACUACAUAACUGUAGACUUAAGUAUCUUUUUGGUGGAAAUAAAAUAUGAAAUCUCUUUAAUUUUGUUAAUGUUAGGUCUGGUAUUCGUUCCAUUAAGUUCCACUUUAAAGUAUGGAAAAAUGUUAUAAACAUCUGCUUUAAACAAUGAAUGGUACUGCAAUAGUCCUGUAAAGAAAAAUGAAUGGAGUAAAGUCCUUCAAGUUUUCAUUUAAAGAAUGGCAUAGCUUUAUAAUACAUUAAGUUUUUAAUAUGCGGAAUGUAUUUAAUAUCCUAAAGCGAUGAAUUGUCUUGGCAUUAUGCUAUCUUAUGAAACACUUUCUUACUCUCACAUUGUGUCUUUAUAGUUUUCAAUAUCAGCAAAACCUUUAAAUAGUCUUAGUUGGGUGUUGUGUAUCAUUGUACAGCAACUGUUAGUACAUGUGGUAUUUCUGAUCCAUGUAAUAAAGUACAUUUGUCAUGUA